AUGAGCAGAUGAGGCCUAGCCGAGGCGGCGGGACCCCCAAGUUUGGAAAGCUCUUUUAACGGCUAUGCGAAAGUUCUGUCCAAAGGCUGCUCACAGCCCCUGUCUGACUGGUUGUCAUGAUGAAUUGAGCUCUCUGUUACCUGCGCAUCACAACCGAUAGUAACUGUCCCUACUGAAGGCCCCAGGAGUGCUCCAGCCAGGUGUGGAAAGCUGGUCACGAUUCUAUGCUACUUGGUUCAUUUUCUACACAGCAACAGAAGAGCCCUCCUGAGAUUGCUAUUACCAUACCCGCCUGUCACCUUGCCAAGGCUGGCCAAUGUGUGUUUUGUCAUAGGCUGUCAUGGAGGCCAUGAUGGAGGAAAAGGAAAGGGGAGGCAGAUGUUGAGGCCCCAGAGGCCACAGUGAGAGCAGUUUAGUUCCUGGGGUGCCAGGACUAAGGGGGCAUUGCCCUGUCCCCCGGAUUACAGUGAGCCACAUGUCAAGCCCAAGAGCCAGGAGGUAUUCUUCCUCUCAGUGUUAAUAAUCAAAGCAUCCUGACACCAGCAGCCAGUUUUUAUGGCAUCCUGGAGGGCUGACCUCAUAGAGAGGCUACCCUCCUUCCUUAGUCACCCAAAGUUGUGAACUAUGAUUGUCAGUUGUGUGUGGGCCAUCUGCCCACUUAGGAUGCAAUUUUUGAUGUGACAGACAUUCCGGAUGUCCAAUUCCCCUGUGAUGAGGUAUGAGCCUUGUCCAGCCCUUUUCCUGAGGGAAGCAAUGUCAGAUGAAAGACUUAGAAUUGCCCAAACUGGCUAGCCAGCUGCCACAUGCACAGUAUUGCUGAUAACUGAGAAAGGUUAGAACAUCGUGUUGCAUUUUGAAUUUCUACCAUUGUUGGAACCAGGUCUAGUAUUAUAAGCCCCUGACCCAGCCUGUGUGUGAGGCCUAAACAAAGCCUGAGCACUUCAGCUAAGACCACCCACCAAGGUGACACCUUUAGCCUCACGCCUUUGAUAAGCUGGCCCAGGUCCCAGUAACUCCAUUGUCAGAAACAGACCCCAUCCCUUCUAGUGGUGCUGCUGCCUUUUGGACACAGAAUCCAGCUCACAGUCCCCUGUGUGGUCCCCUUUUGGCCAUCCUGUGGCUUGGGUAGUAAGAGGUAAGCAUUUGGCUGAGGCAAGUUGUUCAUUCAGAAUAAAUUCACAGCUGCUUAAAUUUUGUCAACAGGCCGAGCGUGUUGGCUCAUGCCUGUAAUCCCAGCACUUUGGAAGGCCGAGGCAGGCGGAUCACGAGGUCAGGAGUUCAAGACCAGCCUAACCAACAUAGUGAAACCCCAUCUCUACUAAAAAUACAAAAAUUAGCAGGGUGUGGUGGCGCACGCCUGUAAUUCCAGCUACUCGGGAGACUGGGACAGGAGAAUCGCUUGAACCCGGGAGGCGGAGGUUGCAGUGAGCCGAGAUCGCACGGCUGCACUCCAGCCUGGGCAACAGGGCAAGACUCCAACUCAAAAAAAAAAAAAAAUUGUCAACAGAGGCAUAACUGAAUGGUGAAACCAGUUUUCUUUUUCAAUUUCUUUUUUUUCUUUUGUGCAGAGCUGAGGCUUCGAAGACCUCAGAGGACUUCUCUCAGCACUCACAGAAACCUCCUACACCCUCGGAUGGCACAAAGGGACUGUUUUCUUACUCUUAGUCUGAGUGACUGCCAAGGAAGGCAAAGGUAGAGCAACUGGAUCUCUGGCUCUCCACAUAGCUUCUGAUCUCAGACCUUACUAAAAUGCUUUCUGGGCCCAAGGACAAAGCUCACAUGAACAAAUGAUUUUGAGUCAUGAAUGAAAAAUCUUGCUCUUUCCAUAGUAAAGAAGAAUUAAGAGAUGGACAGGGUGAAAGAUUGUCUGCUGGAUAUUCUCCAUCAUAUGACAAGGACAAGAGUGUUCUGGCUUUCAGAGGAAUCCCUAUCUCAGAGUUGAAGAACCAUGGCAUUCUCCAGGCUCUGACCACAGAAGCUUAUGAAUGGGAGCCACGUGUUGUGAGUACAGAGGUGGUCAGAGCCCAAGAAGAAUGGGAAGCUGUGGACACCAUCCAGCCAGAGACAGGGAGCCAAGCUAGCUCAGAGCAGCCUGGGCAGCUAAUCUCCUUCAGUGAGGCCCUGCAGCACUUCCAGACUGUGGACCUUUCCCCCUUCAAGAAAAGAAUCCAGCCAACUAUUCGAAGGACUGGGCUCGCCGCCCUCCGACACUACCUCUUCGGGCCUCCAAAGCUCCACCAGCGCCUUCGGGAAGAAAGGGACUUGGUCCUGACCAUUGCUCAGUGUGGCCUGGAUAGCCAAGACCCAGUGCAUGGCCGAGUCCUCCAGACCAUCUAUAAGAAGCUGACCGGCUCCAAGUUUGACUGUGCCCUUCAUGGAAACCACUGGGAGGACCUGGGCUUUCAGGGAGCGAAUCCAGCCACAGACCUGAGAGGCGCAGGCUUCCUUGCCCUCCUGCAUCUGCUCUACCUGGUGAUGGACUCAAAGACCUUGCCGAUGGCGCAGGAGAUUUUCCGCCUGUCUCGUCACCACAUCCAGCAAUUCCCUUUCUGUUUGAUGUCCGUGAACAUCACCCACAUUGCCAUCCAGGCCUUGAGAGAGGAGUGUCUCUCCAGAGAGUGUAAUCGGCAGCAGAAGGUCAUCCCCGUGGUGAACAGCUUCUAUGCCGCCACAUUCCUCCACCUCGCACAUGUCUGGAGGACACAGCGGAAGACCAUCUCAGACUCGGGCUUUGUCCUCAAAGAGUUGGAAGUAUUGGCCAAGAAGAGCCCACGGCGGCUGCUCAAGACCCUGGAGCUGUACUUGGCCAGGGUGUCAAAGGGACAGGCCUCCUUGUUGGGAGCACAGAAGUGCUAUGGGCCAGAAGCCCCUCCCUUCAAGGAUCUCACCUUCACAGGUGAGAGUGACCUGCAGUCUCACUCAUCCGAAGGCGUAUGGCUGAUCUGACCUCCGAGAUGAAUGGAGGCUUAAAGGCUGAGCUGCAGGGGCUUUCAGGGGGUCAGUGGAGCCAUGUCAGGAGCCUGGCCAGGCCGCACCCCUUGCUGUCUCAGCAGAUGGGAUAUAGGAAGCUCCUGGGCUUAGCUGUGGGAAGCCAAGUACCCUCACCGGCAUGGGACAUGAGGGGCAGCUAGACUUCACCCCCUUCCCGCAGACCUGCCUCCAGAGCAAGGAGAAUUCUGCCUUAAUCUGUUGGGCUCCAGUCUCCGGGUUGAAUUCCAGUGUAUCCCACUGGGAGUGAAUGGAUCAUGAGGUGGGAUGGCCCCAUCUGGAUGUUCUGCAGAUCCCCACAUGGGAGGAGAUUCCCAAGUAGAGGCAGCCAGAAUUCUGACUCCCUGGCAGCAGCAGGGCUUUCAGGCACCAGUGUCUGUGUUGUUAGAACUCAGAGGAAGAGGCAGGGGCAGCAGCCGACAGGGGGCAGCAUGACCCAAGCAAGGGGCCUGAGGCCUCAGUGGGGGUAGGGCAAGGAGGUACCUCACAGGUGGGUGUGAGGCCCCCUCUGGAGUUUCUGGCCAUUCACUUACCCACUCUCUUCUCCCCCUGACCCCCGCUCCAUUGUUUAUGAUGGAAAAACGGACAUUUGGCUAGGUGUCUCUCACGGCUGCUCCAUCCUAGCCCCCACAAGCUGGGGCUUCCUCCUGUAGAUGCUGUGCAUGCCCCAUGAUGAGUUUCUGGCCUAAUUGAGGGAAGGAGGAAAUUCAUACCAGCAGUUUUCAAAUAAAAGAAUUGUUCUAA